GCAGCCGCCAUUGCUCUCCUGCCACGGAGGGGAGCGCUUGGUGGCAGUCCGCGGGCCCGGACGGAAGGCUGAGGCGACGCCUCGACGACAGCGGACCGGAGCUGCAGGGGCAACACAUUCAGGGCGGGGUGCCCCAUUUAGGCCUGGCUGACCGGAGUAAGAAACUACAACCCCCGAAGUGCCUUGCGCCUCAAGGUUACGGAGGCAGUGACGUAAGCUGUCUUGACCGCUACCAUUUCUCUAGUAGAGGCGGGACGCGGCGGCGCGGAGUGAUGACGCGCUCUGCUGGCGGCUGGAGGGUUGCGGAGCACCCACCCUGGAGCCAUGGUCCACGCCUUCCUCAUUCACACCUUGAGGGCCCCGAAUACUGAGGACACGGGCCUUUGCCGAGUGCUGUACUCCUGCGUCUUCGGUGCUGAGAAGUCACCUGAUGACCCACGGCCGCAUGGUGCCGAGAGGGACAGGCUUCUCCGGAAGGAACAGAUUUUAGCUGUGGCCAGGCAGGUAGAGUCAAUGUGUCGGCUGCAGCAGCAGGCAUCUGGCCGGCCCCCCAUGGACCUGCAGCCGCAAUCCUCAGAUGAGCAAGUGCCGCUGCACGAGGCCCCACGUGGGGCUUUCCGCCUGGCAGCAGAGAACCCUUUCCAGGAGCCACGGACGGUGGUGUGGCUGGGCGUGCUCUCGUUAGGCUUUGCCCUGGUGCUGGAUGCCCAUGAGAACCUGCUACUGGCUGAGGGCACGCUCCGGCUGCUGACACGCCUCCUCCUUGACCACCUCCGGCUGCUGGCGCCCAGCACCAGCCUUCUGCUGCGGGCUGACCGCAUUGAGGGCAUCCUCACCCGCUUCCUGCCACAUGGUCAGCUGCUUUUCCUCAACGACCAGUUUGUCCAAGGCCUGGAGAAGGAAUUCAGUGCCGCUUGGCCCCGCUGAUUCCUCGUUGGGAUGGUGCUUCUGAGGGCAGGCAGAGGGUAGACACACAGCCAGAUGAAGCUUGGCAUCUCCCUCCUACCCAGCAGCUCUGAUGUGCUGCUAUACCAGGACAAGUGGGUGACACAAGCCUGCAGAAAGGGGGCUGGGCAGAGGGUGGAGGAGGUCCUGCCUGUCCUCAGGUUAGUGGAACCACAGAACUUCCUGAGCCUAGAGCUGCUGUGUUACUUAGACCGCUGCCGUGCGGCAGCCACGCUUGUCCUUGAACCCACCUUCCUCCAUCCCUGCCAGCCGAUAGUGCUAGGGUGAGGAGCUGCCUGGAGCUCACCCCGCUCUUCUUCCAAACCCACAGUCAAGGCCAGGCGCGGUGGCUCACGCCUGUAAUCCCAGCACUUUGCGGGGCUGAGGUGGUUGGACCACCUCAGGUCGGGAGUUCAAGACCAGCCUGGCCAACAUAGUGAAACCCCAUCUCUACUAAAAAUACAAAAAUUAGCUGGGUGUAUGGCGCCCACCUGUAAUCCUAGCUGCUCAGGGGGCUGAGUCAUGGGAAUCACUUGAACCUGGGAGGCAGAGUUUGCAGUGAGCCGAGAGUGCGCCACUUCACUCCAGCCUGGGCAACAGAGUGAGACUCCAUCUCAAAAAAAAAAAAAAAAUCCCACAGUCAUCGAAACACAAAAGGGGUCUCAGACUCCCCUGAGGGUGGAGGAGCUGUGCCUGCAUGCUGGCAGGCCACAGCCCCUGGCUUUGUGCCCACUUAGGCAGUAUUAUCAACAAGGUCCUGCUCAGUGUCCAGCCCCCGCUGAGUUCAGAAAUGCAUCUGCCAAUCAGCAGCAGGAUUCUGCAGCUCCUUUUGUGCCAAGCCCGUUCCCACCAGGCAGGCUCGAGAUAAAGUCAUCACAGCCUUCCCUCAUCUGCAGGGAGAGAAGUUGCUGUCAGAUGAAUGUGAGCAGUCUAGCCUGGAUGACAUAUUUUUCGUUUUGAAUUAAAAGCACUGGCUGUGUGAUUUUACCCUCUUUCUGUGAGUUUGAUGCGUGCAUCCUGCUCCUAUGAGUGAGUGCCUCUCUGGAUGGCCCCAAAGCUGCGUGUCUGAGCUUUCGUGGUCAAGGAUCCCCCUAGGAGGCUUCUUGGGAUGCCUCCAUCUCUCAUCCCCACCUCACCUCUGUCUCCUUAGAGGCCUCCUUUGGAUGGUGGCACACAUUUCUCCACCAAAGUAUAUGUCACAGGUGGCAGGUGGCUGUGGCAGAGCCGUCUGAGAAGCAGUGCUUGGGCUGAGAAUUGGUGCGAGUGGUUUAUGUGGGGUGGGCGGUGAUCCCGGGAAGCAGGAAGGGGACACAGUCCUCGUGAAUGCUUGUCAAGCCUAUUAGGACUGUGGUAGGGAGCUGAGUGCCUCUAGGGGGCUGCACACAGCAGUUGCCUCUGAAUUACCUCACCUGAGAGGUGGCGGCUGUGGGUGUUUGCCUACUGCCUUUAGUCAGUGGUUACAGGUUGAUCCCAGGGUGCAUACAUUCCCUGGCUCUUUCUGCCCCUGAGAAAAAGCCUUCAGGCAAUGUGGAGCUGGGCCUGCCUGCACCAUGUUGAGUCCCAAAGGGAUAUGGGUGGGGUACCAAAAGUCGGUGGUUAGGAGGUCUUCAAUCAGCAGCUUCUAGUGAAGGUUUAAACUUACUCAGUUGGGGGCGGGGGGUGGGGGAAAAACCACUUCAGUUUACAUUGAUUUUCAUGAUCUUCCUGUUACCAAGGAAGGUGAGGCUUUCUUGGCAGAACGAGCCUCCUAGGUGCUCAGCUCUCAUGCUUGCCAUCCAUCAGUUGCCCUUUAGCAUCCAGGAUGGACCCAACUACACCCACUUUGGAGGCAGCACUGAUGAUUAGCCCUUCCAAGUCCAUGGCCAAGGCCACCAGCCAUGCCAGGCCUUCUACCACCACUGUCAACAUAAUUGGGAUGAGGCCACCUUUUCCAUUUUAUGGUGCCACAAACCACCUUGACCAUGAAGACCUAAAGGGAUGUUACUCUGUGUGUGUGGCCAAGUCCCACCAGUGGAAAUGUCCCACAGGCCUCUAGUAGGGACACCCCUUCCCUAUACAUUCUGUUCUCCUGGCCCACCCCUCACCCCAGGCUGGCGGUCCUGGUGGAUUGGCUGUGUUCUCAGGGAACAGGCCAUUUUGUCCUCUAUGGAAAGGCUCAAGCUUACUGAUCUGAAUUCUUUCUGCCUUUUUUUCAAACGGAACUUAAGGAAGAGGUUGAGACUCUGCUCCCCUGGGAGCUGUGGGAAGUUGAGGUUAGGCGUGGCUGGUGGCCUGGUUCUCAUGAGGUGGGGCAAACUGAUGGACAAGAGAAUAGUAGAGACUGAGACCACACCGUGGGGCUGCUGAGCUCCAGUUCCUGUCCAGCUGGACCAGGGUUUUCUUAACCAGAUGAGCUUGCCCAGCACCCUUCCCACACUUCACACUUCUGCCCCAGCCUCUUGGGCUGGGUUUCCACCACAAUUUAUGCUCACCAUAUAUUUAUCGAGCCUCCCUUGGGCCUGAUGCUCUGCUGGGUGCAAUGCAGGAUACAGAAUGACCCCAAAGUUCCAGGAGAGACAGAGCUAAGGCCAGGUGACUGCAGAUGACUGCAAAGCAGCAAUGGUUUGAGCAUCCCUGAAUUGCUGCUCACAAGUGCUUUAAACACCUAAAGGAAGAAGGGGCACUUCAGUGACGAAGGCCAAGUGAAGGAGCCAGGAUUUAGAACUAAAAGUGAGAUGGCUAUGGAAGCAAACUUGCCUCCCUCUCCAAGCCUCUUCCCUUUCUUCUCCCUGCCCCAGGAACCCUGGCCAAACCACAUAUCCCUCAGCUUCUUGAGAGAACUAGAGACUUUGAGCAGCUAGUAGUGUUACCAGUGUACCUCCACAAACACUCCUGGGACAACAGAUGAUGACAGGAGGGCAGUAGAGCCCAGAGAAGAGAGCUUACCUGGAAGGAGGAAGAAGUCACAGGUUUUGUUUUGUUUUGUUUUAGGCGGAGUUUCUCUUUGUUGCCCAGGCUGGAGUGCAGUGGCGCAAUCUCGGCUCAUUGCAAGCUCCGCCUCCCAGAUUCACGCCAUUCUGUCUCAGCCUCCCAAGUAGCUGGGACUACAGGUGCCUGCCACCACGUCCGGUUAAGUUUUUCUAUUUUUAGUAGAGACGGGGUUUCACCGUGUUAGCCAGGUUGGUCUACAUCUCCUGACCUUGUGAUCCGCCCGCCGUGGCCUCUCAAAGUACCGGGAUUAUAGGCGUGAGCCACCACGACUGACUGGCAUGAAGUCACAGGUUUUAAGGCAGGAACUGGCCUGCAUGUAUGUGGGUCACUGAUUGGGUCACAUACACUGCAUGUAUGUGAGCCCUGGGAUGGGAUUGGAUCAUCUUGUCUCCUUUAGGGCAGGGUGUUUUUUUCUAGCCCUGUGGUGCUGCGCACUGUCCAGCAUCCCCCCAGGGCUCAAUGUUUUCUUUUCUUUUUCUUUUUUUUUUUUUUUUGAGAUGGAGUCUCACUCUGUUGCUCAGGCUGGAGUGCAGUGGUGCAAUCUUGGCUCACUGCAACCUCUGCCUCCUGGGUUCAAGCAAUUCUACCGCCUCAGCCUCCCAAGUAGCUGGGAUUACAAGCAUGUGCCACCAUGCCUGGCUAAUUUUUGUAUCUUUAGUAGAGACAGGGUUUCACCGUGUUGGCCAGGCUGGUCUCGAACUCCUUACCUCAGGUGAUCCACCCAUAUUGGCCUCCCAAAGUGCUGAGAUUACAGGUGUGAGCCACCAUGCCUGGCCUCAAUCUUUUCUUUUAAACAAUUAUUCCUAUAUUUUAUUGUAAUGCAGUUAACCGUGUUUGUCAGAUUCAAUACUCUGUGACCCGUUAACCAAGUCUCUGUAUGUUUAUUACUGCAAUUCAAGUGGCCGUGACCGUUUUCUUAAAUAUACUUUAUUUGUUUAGUGCAAUUUUAGGUUCACAGUAAAACUGAGCAGAGGGUACAGAGAGUUCUCAUUUACUCCCUGUCCCCACACAUGCACAGCCUCCCUUAUCACCAACACUGGGCACCAGAGUGGUCAUUUGUUACAACUGAUGGACCUUCAUUGACACGUCACUAUCACCAGAGUCCAUAGUUUACAUUAGGGUUCACUCUUGGGGUGGUACAUUCUAUAGGUUUGGAUGUAUUUUCAGUGACAUGCAUCUACCAUUAUAGUAUCAUACAGAAGAGUUUCCCUGCCCGAACAGUCCUCUGCUGCACCUGUUCAUUCUUCCCUCCCCUCAACCCCUAGCAACCAUUGAUCCUUUUACUGCUUCCAUAGUUUUGCCUUUUCCAGAAUGUUGUGUAGUUAGAUUCAUACUGUAUAUGUAGCCUUUUCAGAUUGACUUCCUUCACUUAGUAAUGUACAUUUAAGAUUCCUUCAAGUCUUUUCAUGGCUGAAUCAUGAGCUUGACAGCUCAUUUUGGAAGUACUGCUGAAUAGUAUUCCAUUAUGUGGAUGUACAUUAUCUGUUCACCUACUGAAGGACAUCUUGGUUGCUUCCAAGUUUUGGCAAUUAUGAAUACAACUGCUACAAACA